AUUGACAGUGCCAAAGCUCGGUACUGGACACAACGAGGGACCUGGGUCUACGAUAACGCGCUUUUGCUCCUCCUGAAGUGUCUUUGGUCCAACGUUGUUCCAGGUUUGUCACCGUUUCUCUCCGGCCGGUCAGGGCAAGAGCCAGAGUGUACCAUGGCUUCCAGUAACACUGUGUUGAUGCGGUUGGUAGCCUCCGCAUAUUCUAUUGCUCAAAAGGCAGGAAUGAUAGUCAGACGUGUUAUUGCUGAAGGAGACCUGGGUAUUGUGGAGAAGACCUGUGCAACAGACCUGCAGACCAAAGCUGACCGAUUGGCACAGAUGAGCAUAUGUUCUUCAUUGGCCCGGAAAUUCCCCAAACUCACAAUUAUAGGGGAAGAGGAUCUGCCUUCUGAGGAAGUGGAUCAAGAGCUGAUUGAAGACAGUCAGUGGGAAGAAAUACUGAAGCAACCAUGCCCAUCGCAGUACAGUGCUAUUAAAGAAGAAGAUCUCGUGGUCUGGGUUGAUCCUCUGGAUGGAACCAAGGAAUAUACCGAAGGUCUUCUUGACAAUGUAACAGUUCUUAUUGGAAUUGCUUAUGAAGGAAAAGCCAUAGCAGGAGUUAUUAACCAGCCAUAUUACAACUAUGAGAACAAUGAAAAACAGCAGUUAAGGGAACACAGGAAUGAAGCAAAGGCAGGACCAGAUGCUGUGUUGGGGAGGACAAUCUGGGGAGUUUUAGGUUUAGGCGCCUUUGGGUUUCAGCUGAAAGAAGUCCCUGCUGGGAAACACAUUAUCACAACUACUCGAUCCCAUAGCAACAAGUUGGUUACUGACUGUGUUGCUGCUAUGAACCCCGAUGCUGUGCUGCGAGUAGGAGGAGCAGGAAAUAAGAUUAUUCAGCUGAUUGAAGGCAAAGCCUCUGCUUAUGUAUUUGCAAGUCCUGGUUGUAAGAAGUGGGAUACUUGUGCUCCAGAAGUUAUUUUACAUGCUGUGGGAGGCAAGUUAACCGAUAUCCAUGGGAAUGUUCUUCAGUACCACAAGGAUGUGAAGCAUAUGAACUCUGCAGGAGUCCUGGCCACACUGAGGAAUUAUGACUACUAUGCAAGCCGAGUUCCAGAAUCUAUUAAAAAUGCACUUGUUCCUUAAAGGAAAGUUUCAUUUGGCCGGGCGCGGUGGCUCAUGCCUGUAAUCCCAGCACUUUGGGAGGCCGAGGCAGGUGGAUCACUUGAGCUCAGGAGUUUGAGACCAGCCUGGGCAAUAUCGUGAGACCCCAUCUCUACAAAAAUACAAAUUAACUGGGCAUCCUGUCAUGCGCCUGUCAUCCCAGCUACUUGAGAGGCUGAAGCAGAAGAAUCUCUUGAGCCCGGAAGGCAGAGGUUGCAGUGAGCUGAGAUCGUGCCACUGCACUCCAGCCUGAGUGACAGGAGUUAAGCCCUGUCUCAGAAAAAAAAAAAACAAAAACCCAAAAAGUACUUAAAGUUUCAUUUACUUAGCUAGGAGAAAGACUUGGUUCUCAAAAUAAUACAUUUUAAGAUUAAUUGGGUAGAAUUAGAGUUCCACCUUUAUUCAUUGUUGAGCAGUGAUUUAUAUUUAGUUAUUAUAUUUAGGAAUAGAAAAUAGAAUUAAAUAAUUUAACUUGAUUAAUCAACCAGACCAAUUUUGACGUCUGGAGAACUUAUAAACUCAAUAUGUUAUAUUUGUUUUCCUGUAUUUAGGUGGAGAAAUGAGAAAAAGCUUUAGUUCCAAUUGACAGUUCAGGUCAAUGUUCAAUGAACAUUCCUAUCUUCUAAACCAGAUUUCUCUUUUUUUUUCCUGAGACGGAGUCUCGCUCUGUAGCCUAGGCUAGAAUGUAGUGGCGUGAUCUCGGCUCACUGCAAGCUCCGCCUCCCGGGUUCAUGCCAUUCUCCUGCCUCAGCCUCCCGAGUAGCUGGGACUGCAGGCACCGCCACCACGCCUGGCUAAUUUUUUGUAUUUUUAGUAGAGAAGGUGUUUCACCGUGUUAGCCAGGAUGGUCUUGAUCUCCUGACAUCGUGAUCUGUCUGCCUCGGACUCCCAAAGUGCUGGGAUUACAGGUGUGAGCCACCGCACCUGGCCUAAACCAGAUUUCUUUAGGGCACAAUUUUUUCUGGAAUCUCACUCUUGUUUUUCACAGUAAUUUUAAAAACGUUUCUACUCCAAUUAAGAAUAUAUAUGAUGUUAUUAUAUAUGCUUAUGAAACAGAUUUAUGAGAAAAGUUUUUUUUAAAUAAAUUAUUUAAUCCUAGCUCUUUGUUAUUCACCAGCUUUUUAAAAAAGUGUUUGAAAAUUAUACAUUCUCGACUUUGGGGAUUAGUUUAUUCUUGUGGCAUCAUUAUAAGGCUUAAUUGUGGAAAGCUAAGUACUUGCUUCUAUUCCUUCCAAUGAGAGAUUAUAACAUAAACUAUUAAAAUUAUUCUGCUAAUAUACCUAGAUUUUUAUUUUUAGGUCUCUGUCCAUUGCUUUUAAUUAAAAUUAUCUGUUUUCAAAUCAA